GCGGGCGCCUGGGCCGUGCUGUGGCGGCGGCGGCGGCGGUAGUGGCGGCGGCGGCGGUGCCUGGGCGGCAGCAGCAGCAGUAGCGGCAGCCCUGAGGACGGUGAGACGGCCGCGGCGGCGGCGACAGCGCGGAAGUCGCGCGGGACCCAGAGCUUCCCCCCUGUCGCUAGUGCUGAGGCUUUCGCCUUUCCUACCCAGCUUCUUGCUCACGGCCCGGGCUGGGCUGGGCAGGGCAACGCGCCCCCGGGGAGGGGCGGAGCUGUAGAUAUGGUGUAAGAUACUUCUUCAAGAUUGGACAGCUGGGGACCUUCUUCUGAUUAACCUUAAACCAACUUGUAGCCAUAGAGACACCUCACAAGGUUCCCAUUUUUGUUGUUGUUGUUGUUGAUUUUCUGCUCACACCUUUCCUGACCUUGCAACCAUGUAUGGAAGUGCCCGCUCUGUUGGGAAGGUGGAGCCGAGCAGCCAGAGCCCUGGGCGUUCACCCAGGCUUCCACGUUCCCCUCGCUUGGGUCACCGUCGAACCAACAGUACGGGAGGGAGUUCGGGAAGCAGUGUUGGAGGUGGCAGUGGGAAAACCCUUUCAAUGGAAAAUAUACAAUCUUUAAAUGCUGCCUAUGCCACCUCUGGCCCUAUGUAUCUAAGUGACCAUGAAAAUGUGGGUUCAGAAACACCUAAAAGCACCAUGACACUUGGCCGUUCUGGGGGACGUCUGCCUUACGGUGUUCGGAUGACUGCUAUGGGUAGUAGCCCCAAUAUAGCUAGCAGUGGGGUUGCUAGUGACACCAUAGCAUUUGGAGAGCAUCACCUCCCUCCUGUGAGUAUGGCAUCCACUGUACCUCACUCCCUUCGUCAGGCGAGAGAUAACACAAUCAUGGAUCUGCAGACACAGCUGAAGGAAGUAUUAAGAGAAAAUGAUCUCUUGCGGAAGGAUGUGGAAGUAAAGGAGAGCAAAUUGAGUUCUUCAAUGAAUAGCAUCAAGACCUUCUGGAGCCCAGAGCUGAAGAAGGAACGAGCCCUGAGAAAAGAUGAAGCUUCCAAAAUCACCAUUUGGAAGGAACAGUACAGAGUUGUACAGGAGGAAAACCAGCACAUGCAGAUGACAAUCCAGGCUCUCCAGGAUGAAUUGCGGAUCCAGAGGGACCUGAAUCAGCUGUUUCAGCAGGAUAGUAGCAGCAGGACUGGCGAACCUUGUGUAGCAGAGCUGACAGAGGAGAACUUUCAGAGGCUUCAUGCUGAGCAUGAGCGGCAGGCCAAAGAGCUGUUUCUUCUUCGAAAGACAUUGGAGGAAAUGGAGCUGCGUAUUGAGACUCAAAAGCAGACCCUAAAUGCUCGGGAUGAAUCCAUUAAGAAGCUUCUGGAAAUGUUGCAGAGCAAAGGACUUUCUGCCAAGGCUACCGAGGAAGACCAUGAGAGAACAAGACGACUGGCAGAGGCAGAGAUGCACGUUCAUCACCUAGAAAGCCUUUUGGAGCAGAAGGAAAAAGAGAACAGUAUGUUGAGAGAGGAGAUGCAUCGAAGGUUUGAGAAUGCUCCUGAUUCUGCCAAAACAAAAGCUCUGCAAACUGUUAUUGAGAUGAAGGAUUCAAAAAUUUCCUCUAUGGAGCGUGGGCUUCGAGACCUGGAAGAGGAAAUUCAGAUGCUGAAAUCGAAUGGUGCUUUGAGUACUGAGGAAAGGGAAGAAGAAAUGAAGCAAAUGGAAGUGUAUCGGAGCCAUUCUAAAUUUAUGAAAAAUAAGGUAGAACAACUGAAGGAGGAACUAAGUUCGAAAGAGGCUCAAUGGGAGGAGCUGAAAAAGAAAGCGGCUGGUCUUCAGGCUGAGGUCUUUGCCAUUGGCCAGGUGAAACAGGAGCUGUCCAGAAAGGACACAGAACUACUCGCCCUGCAGACAAAGCUAGAAACACUCACAAACCAGUUCUCAGAUAGUAAACAGCACAUUGAAGUGUUGAAGGAGUCCUUGACUGCUAAGGAGCAGAGGGCUGCCAUCCUGCAGACUGAGGUGGAUGCUCUCCGAUUGCGUUUGGAAGAGAAGGAAACCAUGUUGAAUAAAAAGACAAAACAAAUUCAGGAUAUGGCUGAAGAGAAGGGGACACAAGCUGGAGAGAUACAUGACCUCAAGGACAUGUUGGAUGUGAAGGAGCGGAAGGUUAAUGUUCUUCAGAAGAAGAUUGAAAAUCUUCAAGAGCAGCUUAGAGACAAGGAAAAGCAGAUGAGCAGCUUGAAAGAACGGGUCAAAUCCUUGCAGGCUGACACCACCAACACUGACACUGCCUUGACAACUUUGGAGGAGGCCCUUGCAGAGAAAGAGCGGACAAUUGAACGCUUAAAGGAGCAGAGGGACAGAGAUGAGCGAGAGAAGCAAGAGGAAAUUGAUAACUACAAAAAAGAUCUUAAAGACUUGAAGGAAAAAGUCAGCCUGUUGCAAGGCGACCUUUCAGAGAAAGAGGCUUCACUUUUGGAUCUGAAAGAGCAUGCUUCUUCUCUGGCAUCCUCAGGACUGAAAAAGGACUCACGGCUUAAGACACUAGAGAUUGCUUUGGAGCAGAAGAAGGAGGAGUGUCUGAAAAUGGAAUCACAAUUGAAAAAGGCACAUGAGGCAGCAUUGGAAGCCAGAGCCAGUCCAGAGAUGAGUGACCGAAUACAGCACUUGGAGAGAGAGAUCACCAGGUACAAAGAUGAAUCUAGCAAGGCCCAGGCAGAAGUUGAUCGACUCUUAGAAAUCUUGAAGGAGGUGGAAAAUGAGAAGAAUGACAAAGAUAAGAAGAUAGCUGAGUUGGAAAGUCUCACCUCAAGGCAAGUGAAAGACCAGAAUAAGAAGGUAGCAAAUCUGAAGCACAAGGAACAGGUGGAAAAAAAGAAGAGUGCACAAAUGUUAGAGGAGGCGCGACGACGGGAGGACAAUCUCAACGACAGCUCUCAGCAGCUACAGGACAGUCUCCGUAAGAAGGAUGACAGGAUUGAAGAGCUGGAAGAAGCACUAAGAGAAAGUGUACAGAUAACUGCAGAGCGGGAAAUGGUGCUAGCACAAGAGGAAUCAGCCAGGACCAAUGCUGAAAAACAGCUGUUGCGUGAAAUAUUGCAUGAGACCAGUUAUUUGAACUUUAAGUGGUUCAAGGUGGAGGAGUUACUGAUGGCCAUGGAGAAGGUAAAGCAGGAACUAGAAUCCAUGAAAGCAAAGCUGUCCUCCACCCAGCAGUCUCUGGCAGAAAAGGAAACUCACUUGACUAAUCUUCGGGCAGAGAGAAGGAAACACUUAGAGGAAGUUCUGGAGAUGAAGCAAGAAGCUCUUCUGGCUGCCAUUAGUGAAAAAGACGCCAAUAUAGCUCUCUUGGAGCUUUCGUCCUCUAAGAAGAAGACCCAAGAGGAAGUGGCUGCCCUGAAGCGGGAGAAGGAUCGUCUGGUACAGCAGCUUAAGCAGCAGACGCAAAAUCGAAUGAAGCUAAUGGCCGACAACUACGAGGAUGACCACUUCAAAUCCUCCCAUUCCAAUCAAACAAAUCACAAGCCCUCCCCAGACCAGAUCAUCCAGCCCCUCUUAGAACUUGACCAAAAUAGAAGUAAAUUAAAGUUGUACAUUGGACACCUGACAACCCUCUGCCAUGACCGAGACCCCCUGAUCCUCCGUGGACUCACUCCACCAGCUUCCUAUAACUUGGACGAUGACCAGGCGGCUUGGGAGAAUGAGCUGCAGAAGAUGACCCGGGGGCAGCUUCAGGAUGAGUUAGAGAAAGGUGAACGGGACAAUGCAGAACUGCAGGAGUUUGCCAACGCCAUUCUUCAGCAGAUAGCAGACCAUUGUCCCGACAUCCUAGAGCAAGUGGUCAACGCCCUGGAAGAGUCCUCUUGACCCUGCUUUAUGGGGAAGCCUGAGGUAGUCAACCCAGGAGCCAAGAAAAGAGAACUACGAGGAACAGGUGCCCGGAACCUUCUUGGCACCAAACACUACAAACUUCAUCCCAACUUGCUCACUUGAAGAAGUGUGAUUCCAGCACCGUUUCUACAUCUGCCAUCUUACUCUGCCUUUCUGCUUUGGAUGUGGUCUCUACACUAACCUUCUUGAUGUCCAGGGUAGAUAAAGGGUCGAAUCUCUCUGAAGAACUGCCACCUGGUCAUCAGCAGUGGAGAACUGUGGGAGCUGGUGGCUCUGCCCUGACAGAGAGCCAUGGAGCAGAGGAGCCUCUCACCUCCUGUCCUCUGACAUGAGAAUGAAACCAGGAAUGGACUUGGAGUUCAACAGGCUGAGAGGAUGCCUCCAAUGGACCAGAGAGCUGAGUGUUCUAAUAUCACAAUAGGUGCUUUCUCCUAAAAGGGCAAAAAACAAUCUCAAAAAGAUUAGAAAAAGAGAAGGGGGGAAGGGAAGAGAAAAUCGACUCUUCUUUUUACUGUCUCUUCUGCUUACUUUCCACAUGAGAUGCUUUGUACCGGGGAGCUGUGAGCAGGCCUCACGAUGGCUUGGGAGCACUCGUUCUCCCAAGGUCUGAGUCUUCAUCCAGCCCUGCCUGUCUGUCGCAGCCUUCCUCACUCUGUUCCUCGGCCAGUUAACAAGAAGAUGGUGUGAGGUGUUCUCCACCAGUCUCUCCUGUUUGAGACUGUUGACGUUAUCAUACUGAGGUGUUAGAUCAAAUAUCUCUAAUUGAAGAACAUGUGAGGUUGAAAGAGCACCAGCCAGGGCAACAUAGCGUGACCCUGUCUCUACAAAAAAUUAAAAAGAGAACAUACAAAGUUGACAUAUGAGACCCUGUUGUCCCCGCCUGCAGCUUUGCCCCAGUAACAGAUGCCCGUUGCUCUUGGGCUGGUUUCCCCUGAACACCUCCAAGAGGCUGCCUGCCUUGCCAGCACCCGUGUCCUGAGCUCCUGCAGCCCAGUGGCUGCUGAAGUUGUGAUCCCUCACUCACCCUGCUAGCUUUGCCCUUGACUCGUCUUCUCUGAACCUCAGCCUCGUGCAUUGCCUGGAACCUUCUUCUAGCAUAAAUGAAGGUUUUUCCUCCUACACACAUUCCUUCCUCGGUUAUUUCAUUCAGAGAAUAUUUAUGAAAUGCCUACUGUGUGCAAGUCAUCCAUCCUUGAAAAGGCCACUUCUCAGUGAGGGAGAGAUGUAGUGGAUUCUGUGAGACAUACCUGCUGGAGUUGAAGCAGUAAAUAGCAUGUCCUUCCCCUCCCCGAUCUUAAGGUGUGUUUUCUAGAAAAGUUCCCUAAUGGAAUUCAUGAGUUUGGGGGUCUCAGUCACCCGCUUGCCUGUAGGAUUCCAUUUGAUGAUUCUGGAUUUUUGCUGUUUGUUAUUGCCCUUAGAGGGGCUCUGAGUAUCUACUUGUGGGUGGCCAUUUCCUGACAUCUGCAUGUACCUCGUGGAAUUCAGCCAGCUUCAUGUUGCAAAUCAGAAAGCUGACCCCAAGACUGCAAAUCAAUGAAGGUAUUGGCAUUGUUAAGGACGUAGCGUAGACAACAGCAGUCAUAAAUAAUUAGGCAGGAACUUAACCCAAAUCUAGUUCUUUGACCACCUCUACCACCAGAACCCAGCAGACACUCACAUCUCCUGAUAAGAGUUGCUGGACUCGAUGUUUUUGUUUUGCAUUUUCUCCUCUCCUUCCCCACUUACUCAGAGAAUUUAAAGUCUGUAGAGUCAGCACAGCCCCAUCAGUCCAGGAACUUCCCACCACCAGCCCUUGACUGUCCCAUUAACUGACAUGGUCAGAUUUCCAGCUCCCCCUACUCCCUGCUGUGAAACAAUCCCUCUCCCUGUGAGAGGAAACUGUGGAGCGUUUCUUAUCGAAGGUUAAAUGGACUCUGCUCAUAAACCUCUUACUGAGAUGCUUCCUGAUAGCCAGGCUGGCCAGAGAGGGGUGCAGGGGUUAGAUAGUAAGUGGUGGUCGUUUGUGGUCAGUUACCUCAAUUCUGUUCAUUGCAGUGCCCGUAAACCAUGUAGAAAGCUCCCAGCACUGAAAGGCAGGAGUGUUAGCAUCUCGCUUUAUCCACCAUAACGUAAAGAACUGCGGUGUGAUAACAGCCUUCACGGGGCCACGGUGGAACCAAGACAGCAGGCGAGGCCAUGCCUAAACAAGUGGUCUGGCACGGGCACUGGCCAGCUGCUCUCUCCAAGCAGGUGGCCCAGAUCCCACCCACGUGGACUUUCUCAUCAGGUGCAGCGCCUGCCACUCUCAGCCACUGGGUGUGUCACUCUCCUCUUCAUCUCAGCAUUCUCCAUCACUUCCCCUCCAGAAAAACGGAUGGAAGGAAGCCCUCUGUGACACUGCUUCUGAGAAGAAGCAUUUCCGGGACCGAUAUCAUCUGUCUGGUCUCUGUGAACAGCAAGGAAUCUUCUUGACCGUUCUUGGGCACUGGAGGCUGGCUAGGAGUUCAGUAAUAAACGUGGCCUUCGUGCUGUAGGGCAGAGUGGAUGCAGUUUGUAGCUUUCAGAGUGUCUCAUUGAGUCUAGAUCAUUGAACCAACACUUAACCAAAUGUCCCACUCCCAUCACACUAGGACUUGUCAUUCCAUGCCCCUCUCCUAGUGGUCAUGGUUUCAUAUGGGCAUACAACUGCUACUGAAGUUAUAUAGCCUUGAAAACUCAGUGCAGGUUGCCCUUAAUUUUCCCCAAACCCCUCCAUCGGCAAGUCUAGUUGCCCUUUAGCACCUAAAGAUCUGCACCCCAAACCAAUGUCACCAUAAAGAGGGCACGAAGAAGAGUGGGUGUGAUCCCAACGGGGUUUUGUAACUGAAGAAGCCCAGUGUGAGCUUCUCAUCUUUUCAUAUACCUCUAACCCCCGGUACUCAUUGAAUCAUUGAUGAGGUAUCUCAAUUGAGAUUUGCAAGGACUUUGAUACCAUUUGAAAUGGAAAAAUUUUGAACGGGCUUUAACAUGUUUAAGAAAUAUGGAUGGGGCCGGCCACAGUGGCUCACGCCUGUAAUCCCAGAACUCUGGAAGGCUGAGGCAGGCGGAUCACCUGAGAUCAGGAGUUCGAGGCCAGCCUGGCCAAGAUGGCAAAAACCCCGACUCUACUAAAAAUACAAAAUUAGCCAGGCGUGGUGGCGUACGCCUGUAAUCCCAGCUACUCAGGAGGCAGGAGAAUCGCUUGAGCCUGGGAGGCAGAGGCUGCGGUGAGCCGAGAUCGUGUCACUGCACUCCAGCCUGGGUGACAGAGACUCCAUUUAAAAAAAAAAAAAAAAAAUAUAUAUAUAUAUAUAUAUAUAUAUAUAUGGAUGGGAAUCACCAAAUUCAUCUCAGCUCUAACCUUUUAACCUUUGUCCUUGCACUUUACAAUCUAAAGAUCUACCUGUGGCUCUCAGACUUCCUCACACUUGGGUUUUAGAAAUAACUUGUAAAGCAGACUGGACCCAAGGCCGCCUUCAGUGUCAAGAAGGGCAUUGUGACUUGCCCCUCAAUUUCUGUCCAUUGAAGUCUGGUUUUCCAUGAGGAACUUGCGGGCUCACCCACCCCCAGAGUGAGAGAAGAGGAAGGCGAAGUCAUCACAGACACGGUCUUAGCCACCUGCUGAACUAAUCCCUCCGCUAUUGAGGGUCAGGGUUGUGAGGCAACCAUCAUGUGUCACCCCAAAAUAUAAAUGUUUCUGAGCCGCCCAUCCACUGGCAUUUGGAUUUGCUGCCAGAGUCCUGUUCCUCCCAGAACCAUCCCGCCCUCCUGUUGACCAUGUUACUUGAGUGUAGGCCCGGUGUCAAGACCCUCAGAGUCUUUGAGGAAAGAGCCAAGCAGAGAAGACCGCUGCGUGGAGUGUGACACCACAUGGCAUUUCUCAAGCCCAGCGGACCCUGUGUCAGCAAAUACCAGUAAUUUAACAUCUGCUCCUGGCCUCCUCUUCACCUGCCUGGGUUCGGAACUGAGGAGGAAGGAUGAGAAGAGACUGCAAUGCAGCAGGCACCCUCUGCAGAGUGAGGCCGCCCGUCCAUCACUGCCAGCCCUGGGCUGCUCAGGAGGGGACGUGAACCACUCAAAGGAAUGUCUUAAAGAGGAUCUGGAGUUUCCCCCAUGCAAAUUAGGGAAGAAUUAGGCAAGAAAAGACAUACAUUACAGGGAAAUCCUUCUGAACAAAAUGGCUGUCUUCACCUACUCUUCUUGCAAGAAAAGACAUACAUUACAGGGAAAUCCUUCUGAACAAAAUGGCUAUCUUCACCUACUCUUCAGCAAAAACCGUCUCCAGACUUUUUAGUGUCAAAAAUGUAACCAACUGUCUCCUGAUUUUUUCCAAUGUGUUUGGCAAGUGCUGUGGCCCUGUUGUAGGUACUUCUCCUGACUCUUGGGGGAGAAGUGGUUUUAGGGAUUGAUUUGGGGGAGCGGGUUUUUGUCCCAUCCCACCUCCUCUCUUCUUUCUCUGCUUGUCGAUAUUGUCUGUGUGAUUCAGAGAAUUGGGGCAGUUACAUUGUGUCUGUUGUUGAGAUUAUUAAAAGAUUAAAACGUAGUUGUAGAAAUGAAAAAUUAAACAGCUGUGUUUUAAAAAUGCAAACCAAUAUCUUGUUAAUAAAGGAAUUCAAGCUAUGGGGCAGCCACACUCCCCUCCUCCCAGGCUGGCAUAGGUGGCCCUGGGCUGGCGGCUUAGGAAGCAUGGAGCACACUUAGGGUAGUGCCUGCCUGGGCAAGAGACACCUGCCGAGCAAAAGGAACGAGAAUCUGGGGCUCAGAGCCUCGCAGUUGUGCCAGGAUUUUCCUAUACAUGUUCAGGACCUCUGGGUAGAGGUUUCACAGUUUGUGACCCCAUAACCACCCUCACCCGACGUGGGUUCUAGCUCAGUGUGCCUAAUACUGCAUGGUAACCUGGGCUUGACCCUGAAGCCCCUGCCUGGCAGGCCACAGGACCUCUCCUGCCCACUUGGUGCUAUCUCUUCCAGUGACCACCCAGCACGGGUGAGCACUGGCCAGCCUGGAGCCUGCAAUCCAGGUGGAACAGACUGUCCUCCAUGUCAGUUCCUUCUGGCUUCAGGCCCUCAAUUAUUUCCCUUUGAGCUUUUUUAGACCCUAGAUCUCCUAGGCCCAGGCUCUCUCUUGACCCCAGAGAAGCCACUGUCAGGAAAGGAAGUGAACCCUACUGAAGCCAGAGAAUUCACCCCGGCCAAAGCAGGCCCUCUGGGUCCAGCCCCUCAUUCCACACCACGCCAGUAUUGCAUCCAUCUACUGCAGCUACACAUCCUGAGGGCAGCACCACCCACUCUGGCCUGCUGGCCCAUCGCAGGACUAGCCCAGGCACCUGCCGGGCAUUGCAGGAUAUCCAGUGGGGCCUGUGACUGCUCCCUGAUGCGUCAGAAGAGAAGUGUUGCACUUUAGUGGAGGAGCUGAGGAGCACCUGCCCCCUUGUAGCUUGAGUUCCUUUUGGUAACAGUAGCAGCCUCCAUGGUGGUGUCUGGGAUGCACGUGCACCCGCUGCCUUCAGCUGUAUGUGUGUGUUCCUGCUGGAGUUGUGUUACUGACAGGAUAAUGACAUUACAAAGAAAUUGUGUUAUAUUCAACUUUGCCUUGAUAAUUAUUGUAAACACUUUGUUCAUUUUUUCUUUUUUAUUCACAAACUAAAUCCACCAGGAAAUUAUAAAGUUAUUUAAAAACC